UCCUAUUUUAUCCAGCCCCCACAUAUUUUUAGUAUUCUGAUACAUGGCUGGGCCCAACACCUAGGGGUUGGAAAUCUCCUUUCUCUGCCAUGCUCACAGUGGACCUCAUGACAUAUCUCUGCACGUGUCACUUAAAAGAUGUGACCCUUUUCUGCCUGCACGCUGCCCAUAGGAAAAAUUGUGAAAUACUCAUGGGCCCCCAAACCAGGUGGUGUGUCUCUCCUGCCUAGGCCUUGUUCACAGGGAGAAUUGUGACAUAUCACUGGACUCAGCACCCAAGUGAUUUGACUCUGCUGCCUGUGCCCUGCUUUCAUUAGAGGAUAUUCACAUAUCCCUGGCAGAAAACCAGAUGAUGUGACUCUUCUUCCGGGUCCCUUCUCUCAGAGAAUAUUAUAAUAUAUUCCUGACUCAAGACCCAGGAAUACAGUCCACCAUUAAGACGGUGACUCAUGUACUUGGACCAAACAUAAAGAAGGUCUUGACUUUCAUACCUGGAGCCAGAAAAUGUAUGGAAUUUUGAAUCUCAUUUCUGGACCUGCUUGCAGGCGUGAUUGUGACAUAUACCUUGGUCCAGCACCUGAGUGAUUUGACUAUCCUGCCUGGGUAAAGCCUCAAAAUGGAAUUGUGACACAUGCCUGGUGCAAGCAUCUAAGGUGUGAUUGUGGCAUAUGUCUUUGCCCAUACCCUGAGUGAUUUUAGUUUCCUGCCUGAGCCCAGCCCAUAGAUGGAAUUGUGACAUAUACCAAGGCCAAGCACCAAGGCCUUGCCUACAAGAAAGAUUGUGUCAUAUCACUGAGCCCAGCACCUAUGUGAUGUACUUCUUCUGCCAUAGUUCUCCCCACAUAAGACACUGUGACAUAUUUCUGGGCCAAUUACAUAAGUUAAAUGAGUCUUUGCUUAUGCCUGGAUCUCACCCUCAGAAGAACUUAUGACAUGUUGCUGGACCCAGCACCUAGCUACAGGUGGGAUUGUGACAUAUGCCUGGGACGUGGUCACUGGUACAAUGAUGACACCCACAAACUUCAACCCACAAACCAGGAGAAAUAUUGAUUCUGUCUGCUAGGCUUUGGGCAACAGGUGGGGUAGUGACUCUUGAGAAAGAAUUCAACAUGCCGGUGAGCCUGUGACUUUCAUACCAGGACACCGUCCUUGGGUGGGAUUGGGACUCUCAUUCACAGAUCCGAUAUAUCAUUGAAAUGGGACCAUUGACAUUCACAGAUGUGGCAAUAAAAUUUUCUCUGGAGGAGUGGCAAUUCCUGGACACUGCACAGCAGAAUUUAUAUAGGGAUGUGAUGUUAGAGAACUACAGAAACCUGGUCUUCCUGGGUGUUGGUGUCUCUAAGCCAGAUUUAAUCACCUGUCUGGAGCAAGGAAAAGAGCCCUGGAAUAUGAAGAGACACAAGAUGGUAGCCAAGCCCCCAGUUGUGUGUUCUCAUUUUGCCCAAGACCUUUGGCCAGAGCAGGGCAUAAAAGAUUCUUUCCAAAAAGUAAUACUGAGAAGCUAUGGAAAAUAUGGACAUGACAAUUUACAAUUAAGAAAAGGCUGUGAAAGUGUGGAUGAGUGUAAGAUGCACAAAGGAGGUUAUGAUGAACUUAAGCAAUGUUUGACAACUACCCCGAGCAAAAUAUUUCAAUGUGAUAAAUAUGUAAAAGUCUUUCAUAAAUUUUCAAGUUCAAAUAGCCAGAAGAUAAGACAUACUGGAAAUAAUUCUUUCAAAUGUAAAGAAUGUGGCAAAUCAUUUUGCAUGCUUUCACACCUAACUAAACAUGAAAGAAAUCAUACUAGAGUGAAUUGUUACAAAUGUGAAGAAUGUGGCAAAGCCUUUAGUGUGCCCUCAAAGCUUAAUAAUCAUAAGAGAAUUCAUACUGGAGAGAAACCCUACAAAUGUGAAGAAUGUGGCAAAGCCUUUAAUGUGUCCUCAAGCCUUAAUAAUCAUAAGAGAAUUCAUACUGGAGAGAAACCCUACAAAUGUGAAGAAUGUGGCAAAACCUUUAAUAUGUUCUCAAGCCUUAAUAAUCAUAAGAGAAUUCACACUGGAGAGAAACCCUACAAAUGUAAAGAAUGUGGCAAAGCCUUUAAUGUGUUCUCAAGCCUUAAUAAUCAUAAGAGAAUUCAUACUGGAGAGAAACCCUACAAAUGUGAAGAAUGUGGCAAAGCCUUUAACCAGCCCUCACACCUUGCUACACAUAAGAGAAUUCAUACUGGAGAGAAACUCUACAAAUGUGAAGAAUGUGGCAAAGCAUUCAGCCAGUCCUCACACAUUACUACACAUAAGAGAAUUCACACUGGAGAGAAACCCUACAAAUGUGAAGAAUGUGGCAAAGCUUUUAAAGUAUCUGUACACCUUACUACACAUAAGAGAAUUCAUACUGGAGAGAAACCCUACAAAUGUGAAGAAUGUGGCAAAGCCUUUAACCAAUCCUCAGCCCUUACUACACAUAAGAUAAUUCAUACUGGAGAAAGACCUUACAAAUGUAAACAAUGUGGUAAAGGUUUUAGCCAAUCCUCAACCCUUACUAAACAUAAGAUAAUUCAUACUAAAGAGAAACCCUACAAAUGUGAAGAAUGUGGCAAAGCUUUUAACCAAUAUUCAACCCUUAAUAAACAUAAGAUAAUUCAUGCUAGAGAGAAGCCUUACAAAUGUGAAGAAUGUGGCAAAGCCUUUAACAAGUCCUCAAUUCUUAACAGACAUAAGAUAAUUCAUACUAAAGAGAAAUCACAAACCUUAAAGAUGUGACAAUGCUUUUUAUGAAAUCCCAAACUUUUUUAAACAUAAAAGAAAUGCUGGUGGCCAGGCACAGUAGCUUACGCCUGUAAUCCCAGCACUUUGGGAGGCCGAGGCGGGCAGAUCACCUGAGGUCAGGAGUUCGAGACCAACCUAACAUGGUGAAACAACGUCUCUACUAAAAUACAAAAAAAAUUAGCCGGGUGUAGUGGUGGGCGCCUGUAAUCCCAGCUAGUUGGGAGGCUG